GUCUGGCCUGUGUUGGCUGUAGGCAACGAAAGGAGCCCUCCCGGUCUGCGCCGGAUGGCCCCGGGCGGUGACUCGGUCCGGAGCCCUGGAACGCUACGCCCACCUGGCGGAAAGCACCACGGAAACGCAUCCUUCUGUGGCCACUGUUAGGUCUGCCAUUUUACACUUUUCUGAUCUCCUCCUUCCCUUCUGUGAGCUAUGUCUCAGGGGUCAGUGACAUUCAGAGAUGUGGCCAUAGACUUCUCCCAGGAGGAGUGGAAAUGGCUUCAGCCUGCUCAAAGAGAUUUGUACAGAUGUGUAAUGUUGGAGAACUAUGGCCAUCUGGUCUCACUGGGUCUUUCCAUUUCUAAGCCAGAUGUGGUUUCCUUAUUGGAGCAAGGGAAAGAACCCUGGCUGGGGAAAAGGGAAGUGAAAAGAGAUCUGUUUUCAGGUAACUGAAGUGGUGAAAAACUACAGAGGAGAGGACUACUGUAAUUCCCAGCCUUGUUCCUUUAUAGUUUCAGAGUCAAGUGGUGAGAUCAAAGACUUUUCACCAAAAAAUGUCAUUUAUGAUGACUCAUCCCAGUAUUUGAUCAUGGAAAGAAUUCUAAGUCAAGGCCCUGUGUAUUCCAGUUUUAAAGGAGGCUGGAAAUGCAAGGAUCAUACUGAGAUGCUGCAAGAAAAUCAGGGAUGUAUUAGGAAAGUAACAGUCUCUCAUCAAGAAGCCCUGGCUCAACAUAUGAAUAUCAGUACUGUGGAGAGGCCCUAUGGAUGCCAUGAAUGUGGAAAAACUUUUGGUCGACGCUUUUCCCUGGUGUUACACCAGAGGACUCAUACUGGAGAGAAACCAUAUGCAUGUAAGGAAUGUGGCAAAACCUUUAGCCAGAUUUCAAACCUUGUGAAACACCAAAUGAUACAUACUGGAAAGAAACCCCAUGAGUGUAAGGACUGUAAUAAAACAUUCAGUUACCUUUCAUUUCUUAUUGAACACCAGAGAACGCACACUGGGGAGAAACCUUAUGAAUGUACUGAGUGUGGAAAGGCCUUUAGCCGUGCCUCCAACCUCACUCGACAUCAAAGAAUUCACAUAGGAAAGAAACAAUAUAUAUGUAGGAAAUGUGGUAAAGCAUUUAGCAGUGGCUCAGAACUCAUUCGCCACCAGAUUACACAUACUGGAGAGAAACCUUAUGAAUGCAUUGAAUGUGGGAAGGCAUUUCGCCGUUUCUCACACCUUACUCGACAUCAGAGCAUCCAUACAACCAAAACCCCGUAUGAAUGUAAUGAAUGUAGGAAAGCUUUCCGUUGUCACUCAUUCCUUAUUAAACAUCAGAGAAUUCAUGCUGGAGAAAAGCUCUAUGAAUGUGAUGAAUGUGGUAAAGUUUUCACUUGGCAUGCAUCCCUUAUUCAACAUACGAAGAGUCACACUGGAGAGAAACCCUAUGCGUGUGCUGAAUGUGAUAAAGCCUUCAGCCGGAGCUUUUCCCUCAUUCUACAUCAGAGAACUCAUACUGGAGAGAAACCCUAUGUAUGUAAGGUAUGCAACAAAUCCUUCAGCUGGAGCUCAAACCUUGCUAAACAUCAGAGGACACACACUCUUGACAACCCCUAUGAAUAUGAAAAUUCAUUUAAUUACCACUCAUUCCUUACUGAACACCAGUGAAUUUACACUGCAAAGAAAAACUAUGAAUGUAUGGAAUUUUUUAAAAAGAAGUAUAAUGCCUUACUUCAGAGAACUCUUGGAAAGAAGCCUUAUGUGAAAGUGAUGACUGUGAAGUAAUAUGGCCCACACUUUAUUCACCACCCUGGAGAAAAAAAAACCCAGGAAUAUGUGGAAAAGCCAUUAAUAACCACUCUUUUAUUUUUUUGCAAUAACAAGGUGAAAUCAAUAUUGUUGAGAAGAUUCUUCCAUCUGGUAAUGUUGAGAAGACUUCAUUUGGUAGGAGUCCCUUACUUUACGUGUGUAAAUUCCUACCAGGAAAGAAUACAUAUCCAAUAGAUUGGAGAAAGCCAGAGAUUAGCCCUCAUUCCGCAUCUGUCAACCAGGACAGAAAGCAUGGACAAGGGAUGAGCUUUACAAAGAUGAUGCACUUUGGAGAUCAGAAAAUUCAUAUUUAAGCAAAGUGAUACAAACACAGUGAUUUGGGAAUGCCUUCAUUUACAAUGCAAUACUUACAUUUUAAUACUCUUGUAGGAGAAAAAGCAACUGUAUAAAUGAAUGUAGAGUGACUUUCUGCAAUAUUUCAAACCUAUAUCAGAGAAUUACACUGUGGGAAAACUACCAUUGUAAUAAGUGUAGCAAAAUCUCCUUAGAUAUCUGAAAAGUCAUACUGGAUGGAAUCUGUAGGAAACGGUUCUAUUUUGAGGGAAGGGGGAUUCCUUUUUGUUUUUUAAGUGAAUUCAGAAAAUGUUAUAAAUAAAUCUUUUGGUUUAUUAUAAA